GCAGGACGUCACGGAGGACUGCAGGGGCCUGAGCCGCUGCUGCCGCCGCCGCCGCGCAGCCCCACAUCAACGCACCGGGGUCCUGUCACCGCCACCGCCAAAAAAGUCACCGCCGCUAGGGUCGCCGUUGCAUCGGUGCAGGGCAAGAUGGCAUCCGCCACAGACUCGCGCUAUGGGCAGAAGGAGUCCUCGGAUCAGAACUUCGACUACAUGUUCAAGAUUCUCAUCAUCGGCAACAGCAGCGUGGGCAAGACGUCCUUCCUCUUCCGCUAUGCUGACGACUCGUUCACGCCUGCCUUCGUCAGCACCGUGGGCAUCGACUUCAAGGUCAAGACCAUCUAUCGCAACGACAAGAGGAUCAAGCUGCAGAUCUGGGACACAGCAGGGCAAGAGCGGUACCGGACCAUCACCACCGCAUACUACCGGGGCGCUAUGGGCUUCAUCCUCAUGUAUGACAUCACCAACGAGGAAUCCUUCAAUGCAGUGCAGGACUGGUCCACCCAGAUCAAGACCUACUCAUGGGACAAUGCCCAGGUGCUGCUGGUAGGAAACAAGUGUGACAUGGAGGAUGAGCGGGUGGUGUCAUCAGAACGUGGCCGGCAGCUAGCUGACCACCUUGGGUUCGAGUUCUUUGAGGCAAGCGCCAAGGACAACAUUAACGUCAAGCAGACCUUUGAGCGCCUGGUGGAUGUCAUCUGCGAGAAGAUGUCCGAGUCGUUGGACACGGCGGACCCUGCGGUCACAGGCGCCAAGCAGGGCCCACAGCUCAGUGACCAGCAGGUGCCACCGCACCAGGACUGCGCCUGCUGAGAGCCAUCCCACUCCCUUUCCCCUCUUCCCUGUCUUCCCCACCUUCCCCCAACUACCCGGGCCUGACCCGGCCCCUACCAGCCACGGGCACAAGACCCCUGCUCCUGACUUAGCCCGUCACCCUUAUUUAUUAUUGUAGCUAUUUAUUUAUUUAUUGAAGAUGUCCCCCAGGGGCCCAGGCUCCCCUGCCCGCCCCAAGCCCUGCCCCUCCUGUACAUAUAGCCCUUUCCCCACUCAGCUGUGGUGUCUCGUGGCCCCGUGAACUCACCGCUCACCCUCCUGAACCCCCCCCCCCCGCCUUUUUUUAAAAUUCACCCCCAUCCACAGUUGUCAGUUGUGAAGAGGGGCCAGAUGACACCCUAAAGCAGGCUGAUCGGGCAAUGGGAGGUGGCCAGGCCUGCCAGCCCCUCGGCUCUGCCGCGGUGGGCCGAGGCCGCUGUUGGGGGUUUCCCUGUGUGGACCAUGGGGAUCAGAGUCUGGCCUGCCAGGCUCCUCUCCCCGUUUUCUCUUUUGGUGGGGGGGUGUGCUGUGGGUAUUCACCACCCUGGGACCCCCCCCCCCCCCGCCCACCAGACCUGUUCUGACCUCAUGAGUGUCAAACGUGCCCCCCAGUUCCUUAGGAGAUGUCAUGACAACACUACACGCACCCAAUAAAGCGAAUGGACCAUCCAUGUGUGUCCCUGUGA